GGUAGGCGCGGGGCGGUCGGCUGCGGUGGCGGCGUUUGGAUGAUUGUCUCUCGGCGGCGGAGUCGCUCAAUGUACUUCUCCAGUUCCUACCCUUCCUCAAGUGGGGAACUCAGGAGACCAAGCAGGGGCAACUGUACUUCGGAUGGUCAGGCCCCAGGAUACUGUGGCGUAUGAGGACCUGUCUGAGGACUAUACUCAGAAGAAAUGGAAAGGUCUCGCACUCAGUCAGAGAGCCCUGCACUGGAACAUGAUGCUGGAAAAUGACCGUAGCAUGGCUUCUUUGGCAGGUAGGAACAUGAUGGAGAGUUCAGAGCUGACUCCGAAGCAGGAAAUUUUUAAAGGAUCAGAGUCAUCUAAUAGCACAUCAGGGGGACUCUUUGGGGUGGUUCCUGGGGGAACAGAGACUGGAGAUGUUUGUGAAGAUACCUUCAAAGAGUUAGAAGGACAACCCUCAAAUGAAGAAGGGAGCAGACUAGAAAGUGAUUUCUUGGAAAUAAUAGAUGAGGAUAAGAAAAAAUCCACAAAAGACAGAUAUGAGGAAUAUAAGGAAGUUGAGGAACAUCCACCUCUGUCUUCCAGUCCUGUUGAACAUGAAGGAGUUUUAAAGGGACAGAAAUCCUAUCGAUGUGAUGAAUGUGGCAAAGCUUUUUAUUGGAGUUCGCACCUCAUUGGUCAUCGGAGAAUCCACACUGGAGAGAAACCCUAUGAGUGUAAUGAGUGUGGGAAGACCUUCAGGCAAACCUCCCAGCUCAUUGUUCAUCUCAGAACCCACACAGGGGAAAAGCCCUAUGAAUGCAGUGAGUGUGGAAAGGCCUAUAGGCACAGCUCCCAUCUCAUUCAACACCAGAGACUCCAUAAUGGGGAGAAACCCUAUAAAUGUAAUGAAUGUGCAAAAGCUUUUAAUCAGAGCUCCAAACUCUUCGACCACCAGAGAACCCAUACUGGGGAGAAACCUUAUGAAUGUAAGGAGUGUGGGGCGGCCUUUAGUCGGAGUAAAAAUCUUGUUCGACAUCAGUUUCUGCACACUGGUAAGAAACCUUAUAAGUGUAAUGAAUGUGGGAGAGCAUUCUGUUCCAAUAGAAAUCUCAUUGACCAUCAGAGAACCCACACUGGGGAGAAGCCUUAUAAAUGUAAUGAAUGUGGCAAAGCCUUCAGUCGGAGUAAAUGUCUUAUUCGACAUCAGAGCCUCCACACUGGGGAAAAGCCAUACAAAUGUAGUGAAUGUGGGAAAGCCUUCAAUCAGAUCUCUCAACUUGUUGAACAUGAGCGAAUUCAUACUGGAGAAAAACCAUUUAAGUGUAGUGAGUGUGGUAAGGCAUUCGGUCUGAGUAAAUGUCUUAUUCGGCACCAGAGGCUUCACACAAGUGAAAAGCCCUAUAAAUGCAAUGAGUGUGGAAAAUCCUUCAAUCAAAACUCAUACCUCAUUAUACACCAGAGAAUUCACACUGGUGAGAAACCCUAUGAAUGUAAUGAGUGUGGGAAGGUCUUCAGUUAUAAUUCUAGUCUUAUGGUACAUCAGAGAACCCAUACUGGGGAAAAACCCUAUAAAUGCAAUAGUUGUGGGAAAGCCUUUAGUGACAGCUCACAGCUUACUGUGCACCAGAGAGUCCACACUGGAGAGAAAAACCUUAUGAAUGUAUUGAGUGUGGGAAAGCCUUUAGUCAGCGUUCCACUUUUAAUCACCACCAGCGAACUCAUGCUGGAGAGAAGCCCUCAGGUCUGGCUCGGUCAUCUUCUUAAGGCAUGGUUUUCUGAGACAGACAGCAAAGACCUUUGAGUUAAGCUGUCUUUAUAAGAAGGAUGUUCAUCAUGGUCUCCUUGGAGACCACUAAUCACAGUGGAGACCAUACCUACUUGCUUUUCCUUGGGUCACUAAGGUGGGAGAGUAGGUGCAACUUAGUCUGAUCCUUACUUAGUAGGAAAUUGGGGAUUACAUCUGUCAUUAACUUGUAGGUUCCCUUCUUUCUCUUAAAAAACUAUUUAAAACUCUAUCUUGUUAGUAUGCAUUCCAUAAUCAGAUUCUGCAUUUCUCAAGAACAGCAGUUAUAUUACCUUUAUUCUAUUGCAGUUCCUCCACUGAACCAUUUACGUGAAGUCACUUUUUAAGUCAUUCUGCAAGAUUAUUCUUCCCUGCUCCUUGGCUAUCUCCUUCCACAGCUACUUUAAAAAUUUGUACUGUAAGCUACAUCCUCUCAUCAUUUUUGUGUUUUCUAGCUAGAAAACUUUUUCUUCCUGUUUGCUAAUCACUUCCUUCACAAUGUUCAAGAUUUAUGCCAUUUCUGAAAGACUUUCUUCUUCAAAUAGUUUUUCGUUUCUUUUAUACCUCUAUUGAUUUGGCCUUAAUGCUUUAAAUUAGCUGGUGCUACGAUGUGUAACUGUUAAAUGUUUUUGUAAAUUGUUCUUAACUUACAAGGUGAUAUGUGUAUCACAUAUGUACAAAGUAUACACAUAUAUAGUUGUGUAUGUGUAUACUUUCUUUUUUUUUUUUUUUUUUUUUGAGACAGAGUCUCAGUCUCCCUCUUGUUGCCCAGGCUAGAGUGCAAUGGUGCAAUCUUGGCUCACCACAACCUCUGCUUCUCGGGUUCAAGCGAUUCUCCUGCCUCAGCCUCCCGAGUAGCUGGGAUUACAGGCAUGUGCCACCAUGCCUGGCUAAUUUUUUUUUUUGUAUUUUUAGUAGAGAUGGGGUUUCUCUAUGUUGGUCAGGCUGGUCUUGAACUCCCAAUCUCAGGUGAUCCGCCCGCCUCAGCCUCCCAAAGUGCUGGGAUUACAGGUGUGAGCCACUGCACCCAGCCUCAAAUGUGUAUACUUUCAUACCAGCUUGUAAGCUUCUGAGAUCAGGUAUGGUAUCUAUUUCUUUAUAUGCAUAAUAGUUUGAAUAUGCUAGUUCUUAAGUUUUAAAAUUCAAAUUGAGCCAUCAUAAACGUGGGCACAGGCUCCCGUCUCCCUCCCAUUACACUGGACUAGAAGCUUCUAAAGAAGGAAGUGGCAUCGUAAUAUAUCACAUAUAAAGGCUCACUGAUAUCUUCUACUUGUAGCCCUGGAAGUCUUACUACUGGUACUUCAGCCUUGAAGAGCUAAUGGAUUUGUGUGUGAAUGAGUGUCUGUUUAUCUAGGUAUUGGGUUGGGCAGUCAUAUCCUACUGAUAACAUGCUUUGAGCUGCACACUUACUCCAUUUCUGAACUAUUUGACUGCAUCCUGCUUCCUAAAUAAAAGUUAUAGUCGGCCAGGCUCAGUGGCUCACGCCUGUAAUCCCAGCACUUUGGGAGGCCGAGGUGGGCAGAUCACUUGAUGUCAGGAGUUCGAGACCAGCCUGGCCAACAUGGUGAAACCCCAUCUCUACUAAAAUACAAAAAUUAGCCGAGUAUGGUGGUGUGCACCUGUAAUCCCAGCUACUUGGGAGGCUGAGGCAGGAGAAUUGCUUGCACCUGGGCAGAGGUUGUAAUGAGCUGAGAUUGUGCCACUGCACCCCAGCCUGGGUGACAGAGUGAGACUACAUCUCAAAAACAACAAACAAAAAAAACCUUACAGUCAAAAUUUACUGCAAGAAGACUUGACUUUCAUGGCUGUAAUAUAGAUGAUUGAAAAUUUCAGCUAGCAGCAUUCCUGGAUGAUUGGAAUUCAGAGUGAUGAGGUUUUUGGUAAAAUAGUAGUAUCAAACUAAUCUGUUUUCCUUAUCAGCUAGUCCUUUCUCACUACAACUGCUGUCUUAAUUUCAAGAUGAGAACUGUGCCUUAAUUAUCUUCCAGACCACCUUUCCUUCUGCAGUCAUAUGUCAGUCCAUGAGCUUGAACCACCUUUCCUUCCACCCUUGCAAUAAUGGCCCAGUGCCGGUGGACCUUUUACUCUAAUGUUCACCCUGUUCUCUUUCCAUCCCCAGACUUUUUUUUUUUUUUUUUGAGACGGAGUCUUGCUCUGUCGCCCAGGCUGGAGUGCAGUGGUACGAUCUCAGCUCACUGCAAGCUCUGCCUCCCAGGUUCAUGCCAUUCUCCUGCCUCAGCCUCCCGAGUAGCUGGGAGUACAGGCGCCCGCCACCAGGCCCGGCUAAUUUUUUUUGUAUUUUUAGUAGAGAUGGGGUUUCACCGUGUUAGCCAGGAUGGUCUCGAUCUCCUGACCUCGUGAUCUGCCUGCCUCGGCCUCCCAAAGUGCUGGGAUUACAGGCAUGAGCCACCACGCCUGGCCUCCAUCCCCCAGAUUUCUUAACAGGCUGACAGGAUCCGCAGUAUGACAAAGGUGGAGGAGGAGGCUAGAGGGGCAAUGUCAGUCAUGUAACCUGGAGGGGUGAUUUUGUGCACUGUGGUGUAUGUUUCAGACAAUGCAGGAGAAAGGAAAGAGAGUUGAGGAUCAAGAAAAUUAGAAUUAAAUGUGAUUGUUGGGGAGAUGUCUCAGACAAAGUUAGAAAGGAUUACUGGGGGCCUAAAGUUUUUCAGGGCCUUUUGAAAUUUCUAAACUUGUCUGGGCACAGUGGCUCAUGCCUGUAAUCCCAGCACUUUGGGAGGCUGAGGCGGUCAGAUCACCUGAGUCCAGGAGUUUGAGACCAGCCUGGCCAACAUUGUAAAACCCCGUUUCUACUAAAAAUACAAAAAUUAGCUGGGUGUGGUGGUGCACGCCUGUAAUCCCAGCUAUUCAGGAGUCUGAGGCAAGAGAAUCACUUGAACCUGGAGGGCAGAGAUUGCAGUGAGCCAAGAUCACACCACUGUACUGCAGCCUGGGCAACAGAGCGAGACUCUGUCUCAAUAACAACAACAAAACAACAAACCGGAGCUCAUGACACGGCUGGAAUUUUACCAUUUGUGAAUAUGUAUUUUAAAUGUUUUCAGCUUGUUUUUUUGUAUUUUUUUCCAUUUUCUUUUAAAAGAUAUGCAGAUAGGACUUUUUCCUCUUUAACUGUCUUAUUUUGGGAGCCCCCAGAUUUCAGGGAAGAGCCCCACACUAUAUGAGCACAUGAGUUGGACAUUUCUGGUUCCCCGCCCUGAGUUGGACAUUGCCAGUCAUGUCUGCAGAAGAACCAUCCUGCCUGUUGGAAGCUGCAGUUUUACCUUCUGGUUCUUGCCUGCUCAUCCCCUACCAUACUAAGCCUCCAGAGUGUGGGAAUGUGCACCAUUUCCUAACUAUAUUAACUCACUGCCACCAGUCUGGUGUGGGUGCUCAGUACAAGUGAAUCCUGAAAAAGCCUCAGGCUCUUGGAUGGAGGAAAACUGGCUGCAUUUGAAAGCCAUACUUCAAUUUCUAUUGGUCACUGCUAGUAUAAACUUUAAUUAUUGAUUUAAACAAAUUUUAUCUGGAUCCAAUUAUGUUGAUAAAUUAUUUUUAGGUUUAAUAAUUUGUUAGAUUCAUUUCCUAGCUUUUCUAGGUUUAGAAUAAAUAAUGAUUUAUUUGUCUUUUGAUGUCACUUAUGUUGUGCAUUAGCAAGAACUUCAGAAAACAUGGAACAGUAGAUGUCUUUCUCUUAACGCUUGGGGGAAUGUUUUUAGUAUUCUGCAGUUUCAUAUCGUGUUCAUUGUUGGAUUCUGAUGUUCUGUUAGAUUUAGGAAGUUUCCUUCUAAUCUUAUUUCUAGAAGAAGCAGUGUAGUUUAGUGGUUAAGAGCACAGAUUUUGUUCCCAGUGCCCUAGGUUCAAAUCCUGAGUCCACCACUUUGUUAGGUGUGUGAUCCUGGGCAAAUCACUUACCUUCCUUGUAUCUUAUUCCUCCAUCUAUAAAAUGGAGCUACCUCAUAGGGUUGUGAAGAAUACAUUAUUGUAACAAUACUGGGCACACAGUGCACAGUUUCCCAAUUAUUAUUAUACUUACAGUUUUGUUUUCUGUUUUUUUUUUUGACAAGGUCUCCCUCUGUUGCUCAGGCUGGAGUGUAGUGAUGUGACCAUAGGUCACCUCAGCCUUGAACUCCUGGGCUCAAGAGAUGCUCCUGCCUCAACCUCCCCUAUAGUUAGGAAUACAGGCAUGUGCCACCAUGCCCGACUAAGUUUUUAUUUUUAUUUUUUGUAAACAUGGGGUUUCACUAUUUUGCUCAGGCUGGUCUUGCGGUCCUGGCCUCAAGCGAUCAUCCUGCCUCAGCUUCUCUAAGUGCUGGGAAUACAGGUGUGAGCCACCAUGCCUGGCCUAUACUUAAAAAGUUUUUAUUAGGAUUGGUUGCUAUAUUAUAUCAAGUUUAAAAACUCCAUCAUUGUAAUUUUAUGAGUUAUGGUUUUUUCUUUUUGUAAUUCAUUUUCUUGACAAGUUUGCAAAUAUUUGCAAUUUCCUUGUACUUUUCAAGUAAAAUCUAUUUGUUCAUAGUGAAUUUUUAUUAAGUACAGAAGUAGAUUCAAUUUGGUAAUGCUUUGCUAGCUUUGCAAAAGAAUUUGGAAAAAAUUUUGUUUAUCUUAUUGCUAUGGAGAGUUUGUAUAACAUGGGAAUUGUUCCUUGAAGGCUUGCUAAAAGUAACUGGGCCUGGUUCUUUGGGUGAGGGGAUUGGGAGGGAUAUAUCUUUAGCAACUGUUUUAGUCAGUUUGAGCUAUUAUAACAAAAUACCAUAGAGGAUGGCUUAAACAACAGACAUUUAUUUCUCACAGUUCUGUAGUCUUCAUAAUUCAACAUCAAGAUGCCAGAAUGGUUGAGUGCUGGUGAGGGCUCUCUUCCUGGUUUGCAGAUGGCCCCCUUUUUCCUGUGUCCUCAAAUUUCAGAGAGCAAGAGCACUGGUGCCUCUUCCAAGUCUUUUAAGGGCGUUAGUGAGAGUGACAGCCCCAUUCUCAUGACCUACUCCAAUCCUAGUUAUUUUCCAAAGGCCCCCCACCCCCAAAUAUAACAUUUGGGGUUAGGGCUUCAACAUAAAUAUUCAUUCUAUAACAUUCCACUCCUAGCCACUCUAUUCAUAUCCUUACAUACAAAAUAAGUUCAUUCCAUCCUAACAGCCUCCAAAGUUUUAACUCAUUCUAGUAUCAACUAACAUUUAAAGUCCAAAGUCUCAUCUAAAUAUCUAAAUAUCUAAAUAAAGGCCGGGCAUGGUGGCUCACGCCUGUAAUCCCAGCACUUUGGGAGGCCGAGGCGGGUGGAUCACUACGUCAGGAGUUCGAGACCAGCCUGACCAACAUGGUGAAACCCCAUCUCUACUAAAAAUACAAAAAUUAGCUGGGCGUGAUGGUGUGCACCUGUAAUCCCAGCUACACGGGGAGGCUGAGGCAGGAGAAUCGCUUGAACCCGAGAGACAGAGGUUGCAGUGAGCCGAGAUCGCACCAUUGCACUCCAGCCUGGGCGACAGUGAGACUUUGUCUCAAAAAUAUCUAAAUCAGAUAUGGGUGAGACCCAAGGUUUAGCUUAUCCUGAGGCAAAAUUCCCCUCCAGCUGUGAACCUAUGAAACCAGACAAGUUAUGUGCUUCCAAAAUACAGUGAUGGGAUAGGCAGGAUUAGGUAUUCCAAUUCCAAAAGUGAGAAAUUGGAAGGAAGAAAGGGAUGAUGAGGCUGGGUGUGAUAGCUCAUGCCUUUAAUCCUAGCACUUUGGGAGGCUGAGGUGGGAGGAUUGCUUGAGUCCAGGAGUUCGAGACCAGCCUGGGCAACAUAGGGAGACCUUAUUUCUACAAAAAUAAUAAAAAUAAUUAGUUGGGCAUGGUGGCUUGAGCAUGGGAGUUCGAGGCUACAGUGAGUUGUGAUCGUACUGCACUCCAGCCUGGAUGACAGAGUGAAACCCUAUCAAUAAAAAAUAAAAAAGGAUGGGGGAGCAGGGGGAUGAUGGUCCUAUGCAAGUCUAAAACUUAGCAAGGCACGUUUCAUGAGAUCUUAGGCUCAUGAAUAAUCCUCUUUGGUCCUAUACUGUCCUCUCCAGGACCCCCUGGGCGGUGGUCCUGACCCGAUAGAUCUGCCAGGCAGGGGUGACUCCCCCGUGGCUUUUGUUGGAGACCAUCUGGCCUGUGGAAACUGGGGCAGUAUCCCUCAUGAUCUCUAAAUAGCCAAGAGAAGAGUCAUUCUUGUAUGGAACAAUGGACAUUCACAGCCUUCCUCAUUCCUGGCUUUAGGACUUCAGAUACAAUCAUGUCAGAGCUCAGGGCUUCAACAUAUGAAUUUUGGGGGCACAGUUCAGUCCAUAGCAAUACUUCCAUUCCCCUGACCUGCAACAUGUCCAGUUACUUCGAAAAGUACUUGUCAUCCACUAUAUUAAUAACAUGCUCAUUGCCAGCCUAUGAAACAAGUUGACCACUCCAUACAUAAGGUCAUAGAUAAUAUGACACAUGCAGGUUGAGUUGUCAGCCCUGAUAAGAUCCCAAGACUUGCCCAACAAGUGCAGUCCCUGGAGCUACCUGGUCCAGUAAUUAGAGGAGUAUUCCUGAUAAAGUCAAAUAUUGUCCUUGGCAGCCCCCACCUAAAAGAAGCUCAAUAGCUGGUAUGCCUGUUUGUCUAUUGGAGAUAACAUGUAUCACAUCUGAGUAUUAUUUUGCCUCCUUUAGUUAAAAUUACCCACAACACAGCCACCUCUGAAUGGGGCCCUCAACAACAGCAGACUCGAGAGGCCUACUAUGCAUUAACAUGGGCCUGACAUUAAUGUAGGCCCAUGGAACUACAGGUCUCAUUGACUCUUACCCAUACAGAUUGGAUACUGCGGCAACAAGAGACUGCUAUCAGGAUGCACCAGGCCCUUAGGUUUUGGACAUAUAAAUUACCCAAGAUGGUUGCCAUAUACAUUCCCUUUGAAUGGCAGCUACUAGCCUGCUAUUGGACUCUAAUUUAAACAGAACACUUGACCACUGAAGCACUGUAUGUGACCUUAAGACCUGAGCUGCCCAUCUCAUGCAGGUAUUAUUAACGAAAAAUAAAAAUGGAAGCCCCAGUUUAGAAAUACCCUAAGGCUGACUACCCGCAACCGUGUAACCAAAACUAAUCAUUCUGAUUUUCCUGAAAUGCUGUCUCUGAUCAUAAAUGAAAUGCAAAAUGUAAGCUUUACAUCCUUGCCAGCAUGAUUCACUGAAAUUAAACCAAUCAGCUAUAGACCAACAAGCUUAAACAGCUCAACUUGCCCUAAAAAGAAUGUAUAACAGCCAAUUAUAAAAAAGGUCAAAAUAUUCCCCCCCUUUAUGCAUUAUAAACUGUGUUGUAACUGCUGUAAGAUUAAUUUCUUACCACUUGAUUUGAGUCUUCUAGAUUGUGGUCUGUACUUCUUGUUUGAACAAUAAACUUUUAAAUUUUUCUUUA